AGCUGCGGGCUCCGAGGCCAGAGAGAAAAGACUGCGAGGUGGCCGCAGCUGUGGCCGGAGAGCACAAAGAAUGAACCAGCAGUGGAAGAGAAAAUACUGUAAGCUGGCUGACUGCUGGUGAAGAAAAUGCUUUAUUUUUGUGGCAGGCAUCUGUGGGAUCUGUAAUAGAAAUAUUUCCAAGUCUCCUCAAAAGGAAAAGUCUCUAUAAGAAAAACUGAAGACACAGGAGUUUGCUCAAAGAAUGCUGAAAUAGAUCUCCAGAUAUUGGAGUAAUUCAAGAUUCUGUGGUUGGCCCUUUUGACUGCUCUCUCUACAGGUUUAAUUUGGGCAUUUACUCAUUUUCAUGGCUCCAAGGACCAUGUAUGUGUUGGUGAGUCACCAGACUUUUUUCAGCUCAGAUUUAUUCUUGGAGUAUCAAACUAGUAAAUUCAGCUGUCAUCUACCUAUCUCCACCUGGAGACCUUAAUAAAGUCAUUAUGUCUGAGACAGAACUCUCCUCAAAUUCUGAAUUUUGGUGAAUGUGUCACCAUCCAUCAGUAAUCAAAUGCUUUCAUUUCUUUUUCCUUAGCAUUCUUCUAUUCUAUUGUUGGAAACUUACAUCAGCAACCUCCCUCUAAUUAUCUUAUACUUGCAUUACUACCUGGAUAUUCUAGUUUCCCUUUCGCCAUACCUCCUCCUGCAUUACCAAACUUUCCUCCAACCUGCUGUUCAAAUGGUCUGGAAGCUACUAAACUGGCUGUUAUUUCCUGACGUAAAACCUUUCAGUGAACUCCUCUUGUCUCAUUAGUGGUUCAUAUGUGGACCAGCUUCAUAGAAAUCCUUAAGCCCCUUGAAAUUAUAUGUAGGAUUGUUCCCUUUUUGUGUGUCUGUAAUUGGAUUCUAAAUUCAGACUUUAAAAAUCUGAUUUUUAAUAUUUGGAGUUUUUAUUGCAAGCUAAAAAUUUCUUGAAUACUACACAUACUAAAGAUCUUUUUUGCUUAUAAUAAUUUUGCCUUUCAUUUGACUAGUUGUCCAAGAAGUUUCAAGGAAAUCUGAGUUCUUGGAGAUUUCCACUAACUCUGCCCAUACCCCUCUAUAUUUUGUCUUCUUGAGAAGAAGACUUAGUAUUAAUAGACUCUUAUUAGUCUGGCAGAAAUAUUUCACAUGGUUUAUCUAUUGGAAGAAGGGGAUUUAUACUUAAAAGUUGGAAUAUCACAUGAAGAAUUCAGUAAAAACGUCUUUGAAAGUAAAUGAUGUAUUAUACUUAUUAAUAGAAUUGGACUAACGUCACUCCAAAUUUCUGUGUAUUAAAUUCUUAGUUUAGUAAACUGGAAAUAAAUUCCCUUUUUCAAAAUUAGAAUUUUCUGAGACAUUUAUGAGAUAGGGAAUACCUCUUUUGAUUAGCAUUAAUACUUGCUCUACACAAAGGGAGGGGAAAAGCUUUCUUAUUUACAUAUUGGUAUGAUCAUCUGCAUACAUUUAGUCUCCCACCUAUUUUAAGAUCAUUGGAACUGCAAAACAGAGACUGUGUAGGGUAGAUUAAAAUGGUUUUUUAAAAAGCCUUGAAGUAUGUCUUAUAGGUAGACUAGCAGUUUGGGGUUACUUUGUGUCUAUCUUGUUACACAUUUUAUCUCUAUCUUACUUAUUGCAUGUGCCUCAUUCAGAAUUAAAUAAGAAAUAUCACUAAGUUUUUCUGCCCAUUUGUUAGUUGGUGAUAGACUAACAGUAUACUUGAUGGGCUAAACAGAAUCAGAAUUUAUAAAUUGCUAUGGCAAAUUGAUAGUUAAGAGUGCUUCAGAUGAAAUAAUGACCAUUUAGCUGUCUGGUGUCCAUUGUUUGCAGAUUAACUUUGUCCAACUUCACUUCAUUCUGAUGAUGGAACCAAAAUACCUGCACAAACAGGAUUGUUUUGCCUUUCCAAUUAUGUUAUUAUAAUUCAUGCCUUCUCCUGGGAUGAUUGUAAUUGCUUUCUUAGUUUUGAAAUUAUGUGUUUUGGUUUAUUCAUAAAUGCAAGAGUAAGAGUCAUGCAAAAUAUUAAUCAUAUUAAGUAGGGUGGAGGAUAAUGUUUUUAGGUUGGAAACUUUUUUUUCUGUAGAUAAACGAGCUGUAUGUGAUGGAAAACUGACUUCUUGGGCCCAUUUUACUUAAAGCAAAUACAAUAGGUUUGGAAUUAUGUAUUUAAAAGCAUGGCAUUGGUCCACGUGACAUGUUGGGUGUCUUGUUUUCAUUUUACCAGACUCUGUUUUUAUUUAUGUUUUCAGUUUAUGAUCCUGUCCUUUGUUCAUAAGGUACUUAGAUGGUUUAAGAUGUAGACUUCUUAUAUGAAGAUGUUGCUGUUGUUUUUCCAAAGUAAUGGUGGUCAUCAGCCCAUUUUUCUAUUUAGUCUCAUGAAUAGAAUCAUGAGUAGAAUCUUUCUUAAAUUAUUACUUGUAAAUGGAUCACUUUCUUGUUUUCUUUUUCUUAAUUGGAGCUUUAAAUAAAUAUGGAACUUGGAACAAAAAGAUUUUCAGGAAUUUUAUGGAAACUAACUUUUUUGACCUAAAUCGAAAGGGAUGAAAGUUUCUGAAAACCUAACAAAAUGUGUGCACAGCCAAUUCUUUUAGGGGAGGAAAUAGGCAGGGAAUGUGUAAUUGGCUAUUUUAAAAACAUAUGCCUUCUUUUGUAACUUAUUGUUGUUUCAAGUUACAAGAUCUUUGAAGGCAAGUGUUUAUCUCAAAAUAUUUGAAAGCUUUUAUAGUGCUUAACAUACUAAGACGUCCUAUUAGGGUUUACUUAGAACAAGCUUAUCCAACUUGUGGGCCACAUGUGGCCCAGGAUGGCUUUGAAAGCGGCCUAACACAAAUUCAUAAGCUUUCUUAAAACAUUAUGUGAUUUUUUUUUUUAGCUUAUCAGCUAUCAUUAGUGUUAAUGCAUUUUAUGUGUGGCCCAAGACAAUUCUUUUUCUUCCAGUGUGGCCCAGGGAAACCAAAAGAUUAGACACCCCUGACUUAGAACUUUCCAUAGGUUAGGAGAAAGUUGUACUUUCUUGAUGUCUAUAACCUAGAAUUUCUGGUAAAGGAAUUGAUUGGAAAUGUUAUUAAAAGUUGAAAAUAAUUUGGAAAUUAAACAUUUUAGUGAUCAGUUCUUCCAUUGAGACUGUGUUGGUUCCUUUACUAGAUAUGUGCCAUCUUUUUAAAAACUUACUGUGUUGCUUCCUUUACUAGAAAAUUGCCAUCUUUUUGAGCCUUGUCUAUUGAGGAACCAAGAACACAGAAAAGGCAGUAAAAAGAAAAAAAAGGAUUGUUUGAAGAUUGAAUGUGCUGUGAUGAUAGCCUAGGAUUAUUGUUUUUCAAUUUUUGAUGAGCGGGAUCUUCAAUAUUCAUGUUAUUUUCUCCUUUGGUCUUAUAUGAUUGUUACCUUUAUGAAGCUUUAGUGAUUACAAAGCACUUUUUUUGUCCAUUUUUACCUGAGCUUUGUAAACUCUGAUUUGCAGGAUGGCUGGCUGUGGUGAAAUUGAUCAUUCAAUAAACAUGCUUCCUACAAACAGGAAAGCGAACGAGUCCUGUUCUAAUACUGCACCUUCUUUAACCGUCCCUGAAUGUGCCAUUUGUCUGCAAACAUGUGUUCAUCCAGUCAGUCUGCCCUGUAAGCACGUUUUCUGCUAUCUAUGUGUAAAAGGAGCUUCAUGGCUUGGAAAGCGGUGUGCUCUUUGUCGACAAGAAAUUCCCGAGGAUUUCCUUGACAAGCCAACCUUGUUGUCACCAGAAGAACUCAAGGCAGCAAGUAGAGGAAAUGGUGAAUAUGCAUGGUAUUAUGAAGGAAGAAAUGGGUGGUGGCAGUACGAUGAGCGCACUAGUAGAGAGCUGGAAGAUGCUUUUUCCAAAGGUAAAAAGAACACUGAAAUGUUAAUUGCUGGCUUUCUGUAUGUCGCUGAUCUUGAAAACAUGGUUCAAUAUAGGAGAAAUGAACAUGGACGUCGCAGGAAGAUUAAGCGAGAUAUAAUAGAUAUACCAAAGAAGGGAGUAGCUGGACUUAGGCUAGACUGUGAUGCUAAUACCGUAAACCUAGCAAGAGAGAGCUCUGCUGACGGAGCGGACAGUGUAUCAGCACAGAGUGGAGCUUCUGUUCAGCCCCUAGUGUCUUCUGUAAGGCCCCUAACAUCAGUAGAUGGUCAGUUAACAAGCCCUGCAACACCAUCCCCUGAUGCAAGCACUUCUCUGGAAGACUCUUUUGCUCAUUUACAACUCAGUGGAGACAACACAGCUGAAAGGAGUCAUAGGGGAGAAGGAGAAGAAGAUCAUGAAUCACCAUCUUCAGGCAGGGUACCAGCACCAGACACCUCCAUUGAAGAAACUGAAUCAGAUGCCAGUAGUGAUAGUGAGGAUGUAUCUGCAGUUGUUGCACAGCACUCCUUGACCCAACAGAGACUUUUGGUUUCUAAUGCAAACCAGACAGUACCCGAUCGAUCAGAUCGAUCGGGAACUGAUCGAUCAGUAGCAGGGGGUGGAACAGUGAGUGUCAGUGUCAGAUCUAGAAGGCCUGAUGGACAGUGCACAGUAACUGAAGUUUAAAUAAAAAUGUCUUCAGCUCCAUGCUCAAGGUUGAAAGGGUUACCUGUAAAUUUCUGCCCACAUAACAUUAUACUCAUCCCUAGUAGUGCAUUUUGGGAGUUGGGGUGGGAAGGGGUAUGGGAAGGAUAGACUCAUAAUUAAAAUGUCUAACAUGUCUCUGUUGAGAAAUUUAUUUAAUGUAAGGAACUUGGGUGUUAAUAGUUGAGAGCUGUUUAGUAAUAACCCAGUUUUCUUGAGGUCUGUUUACUUUAUACUUUUUAAAAACUUCUGUAGUUCUUUUGGCCAGUGUGUUUGUAUUAUCUGUGCAUUAAUGGUCCUCAUCUGACUCCUGCAUUGUGUCUUAUUUUUCUGCAUGGAUUGGCAUAAGACCAUUACUAAAAUUUGGCACCUGUGAGAUGUUUGAUAUUAUGAACAGGAAACAUAAUUUAAUGUAUGAAUAGAUGUGAAUUUGGGAUUUCAAAAUAGAUGAAUAACAACUAUUUUAUAGUAAAGUUAUUGAAAUGGAAAUGAAAACAGCCAGUAACUUAUGUUUCAGAAUGUUUGUAACACACUUCAUGGUGUUCCCAUAGGCUUUGCUGUCUAGUCUUAUAGUUUGAGGUUUUUUUGGUCUGCAUUUUUCUUUUUGAUUACAAAAUUUAUAAUUUAAUAAAUACUAGAGUUUAUCAAAAACAGUUUGUCUCUUGUUUGAGGGUGGAAAGGGUGUGGAAACAUUUUGACAUUUGUGACCAAAGGUCACUUAAAAAGUGGUGGUUUUAAUUGGUUGUUUUCAGCUUAAUCACCUGCUCAGAAAAGUUUGAUUUUUUUCUUAGAGAUUAUUUAAACAGAAUCUAUAGGCAGUGUGUAUAUAAUAAACAUGUAUGGAAAUAAAA